AUUAUGCCACGGUACUCCAGCCUUGGGGGCAGAGUGAGACCCUGUCUCCAAAUUUUUUUUUAAAUCUCCUCUGUUACAGGAUAUCAUUGCUACCUUCUAGCUUUUAAUUUGCAUAUAAAUUUAUUAUAGCAUAGCAGCUCACUAAUAUGCAUUUUCCCCCAAACAGUAAUUAUUCAGGCAAAUCUUUAAUUAGAUCAAGGCAAAAUAAAUAUUCAUACAUUCUAAUUUUGAAUUGUUGGAACCUUCUAUUAUAAUUUUAAAAUGAUAAGUUCCCAUUACAAUAUCAAUUCCUUUGUCUAUUGGUUUUAAAAAGACAAGCACAUCAUUUUAUUUGAUAGCAACCUGCACAUAUGAAACUAUUUCAGUAUUUGUUUUUUGUUAAAGUAUAGAGCAUUUAUAUUCUCAGUUUGUUAAAGGUACUCUAUAAGAUUUUUUUAUUUUUUAACCAUGGUGCAUUAGAGAUAAAAUCAAUUACUUUCUUAACAUGUAUAGAAAUACAUAACAAUUACAGUUAGCAGGACAGUUAUUACCUACCAAAGUGGUACAUUAUUCUUUUUAGUUUCUCACUCUUCAUAUAGGAAAUAAACAUUAAUUCAGUGUUUUGUUUCCAACAGUACCCUAGAGCAGUUUCUGCUUGUUAUCCUGGUACGUAUUACCUAACCCUCAUUAGUAUAAACACAAAGAUGUAUUUGCAAAAGUAGUUUUAUUUUCGAGUUCUUCAGUAGGGUCAUGAUAAUAACUCACAGAAUUCUACCACAAGAACUGGGAUAGCAAAGUUGGGUCAUAGGCAGUUAAGUAAUUGGCCUCAGAUAGUUAUCCUAAAGCUGGAAAUUUUUGCAAAGUUAUUGUUGGUCCAAAGAAAAAGCUGAAACAUUAUCCUUAAUUGUGAUAUAAAUGUUAAACUCCAUGUUAACAAGGAGCCCUUUGCCUUAAGACUGCCUCUACAAACUAGGUCAGAACACAAAAAUCCCCCAAGUUAGAGAUUACUUUUGUUGUUUUGUUGUUUGUUUGUUUUUUUUACUGUGCUAAAUUGAAAUUUAUUGUCAAAUACAUAAUUUUUAAUAGAUAUUUUAUCUUUUCAUUUAAAAUUAAUAAAUAGAUAUUUAAUAAAUAUAUAUUGUUAAAGAGAAGUCACUUAUUUGUCUAGACUAUAAUUUAUAAUAUCAGGGGGAUGAUUCAUCAGAUAUUUCCCUGAGAAUAGAUUUCAAUUAAGGAAUUAGAGAUUGAGAAGGAGAGAUUUGCAUGAAUUUGGAUGUCUGGAGAGGGGAGAACUUAGAAAGUGGAGGUUACUUCAGAUAUUUGCCCUGUUUCACAGUCUUGUCCACGUGGGUCUGUUUGCAUUCUGUUUUGGUGGACAGGAAUAAUGCAGCAGCAUCUCUAAGCAGAGUGUUAGAACAUUAGCCGUCCACAAUCCUAAAUGUAGGACAUUGACGAUACAAUUAUCCUUUGCAGUACUGUUGCCUUCUAGUAUGGAACUAAGUCACAUAUAAUGCUGGUUAGUCAUUUAUUAUAUUUGAUGUCAUGUAGCAGAAUUAGUUUAAGAAAUCAUUGGAAAAACACCUGACGUGUGCAUAUGUUUUAUAGUGUUUAAGGUUGUUCUAAAGAUAAUAGACAAAGACCAGUCUUUAACUUCAUUGGAGAAAAAGGUUGACUUUUGGAUUUAAUUACAAUUUAGUUCUAGAUUCCAGAUCAGAUUUUUUUUAUGUUGAAAAACACCAUUUCACCAUGCAAGGCCUCUAUUGUCAGCUUUGUACUUCCAUAGAUUUGGCCAUGCUGAGGUUAAAAUGCAUGUUAGACAUCAAUAUGGAGAUAUCAGGCACACAGCCGAAUGGAGUCUGAAGCUCAGAGAGAGAUCAGAGUUGGAAAUACAUAUGCUGAAAUAUGUAAAUCUUCAGCAAAUAUAAAAGGCAUUUAAAGGCCCAGGGUGAGAUAAGUUUACUUGAAGAAGAAGGAAUCUACUGAAAAAUUUGAACAAUUCAAGAAUGAUUAUCUAGGAACUUCAUUAUUUGGAGGUCAAGUAGAGGAGAAAGAAGGAGUCACUAAGAAAGUAAUAUAAAAACCACUGGAGCAUAUUAUCAUGGAGACCAAGAGAGCGGAGUGUUUCAAGAAGGGGAGAGGAGGUCAGCUGCAUCAUCUGUGGCUAAAAUAUGAUGGUAGAAGCAUCAUCAUUGAUUUUGAUAACAUGGGGUUUUGUAGGUGAAUUUGGUGAGACUUUUCAGAAGUGUGGCAGAUACACAUCAGAUUGGUGAGUACUGAAGCAUGAGUGGUAGGAGAAACAGAGGAAAGCAGAUGAAGUCAGUUUGGCUUUGAAACAGAAGAAAAUAGUUGCUGGAGAGAAUAUGAAGUCAAAGAAAUAAGUGACUCUAAAAGGGAUGGUGGUGGGUAGCAGAAAAGUGGAUUGGUCAGUGAAAGUCAUUAUGAAGUAGUAGAAUUUUUAAAUGUAUUUGAGUCAAUGAAAAGGAUAGAGGAAUAUAGUCAGAGUGAGAUAUGUAUUAUAAAGAAGAUGAAGGAGGCGGGAUAUUUUUCUAAGUGAAUGUUAGGACUAGGGUAUCAUUAUGGGAGUGGGAAGCUGUCAAGUAACGUAAGAAAAGCUUACUGGAGGCGACAAAGUCAAGGAAUCAGAUGUCGGCAUAUUGGGUGGGUCAUUCCCCGGAUGCUGAUGUAACACAGAAGGAUGACAGAGAAGAUACUUCAAUAGAUCUUCAAGGAUCUUCAAUGAAUGACCCAAGUUUUAUAAAUGACACUAGAGGAAAAAAUGGCGGCUAGCAUACUUGGAUGGCAUAAGUAGUUUUUUGUUUUUGUUUUGUUUUGUUUUGCUUUGAGACAGGGUCUCACUCUGUUGCCCAUGCUGGAGUGCAGUGGCACGAACAUGGCUUAAGUAGCAGCCUGGCCUCCUGUGCUCAAGAAAUCCUCCCACCUCAGCCUCCCAAGUAGCUGAGAGUACAGACACACACCACCAUGCCUGUCAGUUUGGGUUUUUAAUAGAACUAAAUGAAUUACAAAUGGGAAAAGUAGAGUGAAAACACUCAUCUUCACCUCCUGGACCUGAGGUACACAGAGUGUAAAAGAAAAUUUAAAAAGCACUCACUAGGGAGAGCUAGUAAAACAAUGAUGUGCUCAGGGUACAUUCACACUUGAGUUAUGGCAAGGGGAAGGACAUAUUUUUAAAAGACAUUGAGGGUAGAGGAACAUUUAGUGAUCAUAGACAUGGGCUUCUGGCAGUAACAAAGUGUUUAGAAUGGAGUGGAGAUGUGAAUGAGGGGAUGCACACAGAACGCACAGGGGAUGAAAGUCUGAGUCAUAGUGAGUGUUAUGAUCCUGGAGGUCUGGUUGCUAGUGACACAAGGAUGUGGGGCAAGAUGAAACUAAUCCCGAGAGCAUCCUGAGCAGAAAUAAGACUGAUCAGUUCUGUCUGUGUGCCUGAAAAGUUAUCUGAUGUAGAUUUGGUGCUCUCUAUGGGAGUACGUGGGGAUGCCAUUGCCCUGGAACUACUGUUUCUGGUGAAGGAUGCUGAAGCUUUGUGGAUUCUUCUUCUAAUUUGCCUCACUCUUGAGUCCUACCCAAUCAGUACAUUUUCGGAGAUGGAAACUUUGUCAGUAUUAUAUCAGCAAACAUGAACACCUUGUGCUUGCUCAGAGUGGGUAAAAGCUCUCAACCUUGCCAAGAUGUGCUUCAAACUUGAUUGCUAUGGUAAUUUUCUUGUGCUUAAUGACAGGGCAAGGAGUAAAGGGAAGAAAUUUUCACUGAGUAUCUAGAUGUGCUGAACUCUGGAAACCCUUGCCUCAUUUAUUGUGGCUUCAAUCUACUCUUCUGCUCAUUUUGUAAGCAAGAGUCUCAACUCUAAUGCUAGCAAUACUUAACUGCAGGAAACGACUAUUAUAACUCAUGUCAUUAUACCCACGUCUUGAAAACUACCAUAUUAAAGGGAAAAAGUACCGGCUCGGGGAGGCUACUUUAUUAAUAUCACAUUACAUUUAAGUCAAAGUAAUGCUGCUUUUGGAAUUUAGAUUUCUUGCAUCCAAAUCUUUUUGAAGGUUAGGAAGCCAUGUAGCAUACAAAUGAAGGUGAACUACAUUAUCUAUCGCCAAAGUUAGACUGAUUUAUAACCAAAUACUAUGUCUGUUAUACUAUUCUUUUAGUAUACGUUAAAGUAUAGAGUUAAAGCUUGAGGAGAUGCUGAGAGGAAUGUUAUCAUGAAAAUAAAAUCUGGCUAGUUAUUAAGGUGCUUCAAAAUUAAAUUUUCACCAUGGUUUGGGUUUGACCUUAAAUUUGUAGGCUAAUGGAUUUCAUCUUGUGAUUAUCUCAAAUAUCUGGUGAACAGCUACUUUGUGGGAAGCUGUACCUACAGAGACAGAUUUAUUGUUUAGUGGAGACAAUAUCAAAUAUCACAUACUUGCUGACUUGAAUGAGCUGACGAUCUUGUAAAACAUACAAUCAAUUGUCAAUUAGAAUGUGCUAAUCAUCGGCAUUGGAACAACAGGGAAACUAAACGUGGGGGCAGGGUAUAAGGGCUCUUAAAUAAAUGCAUAUCUAAGCACCAAUAAAUAAUUUUUACAGAUACCUUGCAUAAAAUCAGCAUUUCAGUUUUUUUAAAUUUACUAUUAAAAAUGCCUGUAUAGAAAAUCAGAUUAUUUUGUGAUCUCUUAAAUGGCAGCAAGUUAAUUAAAAGUUCAGUGUAUUCAAUUGUCAUCUUUUUGGAAGAGAUUGGAUUUUUAAUUAAUAAAUUAACACAUUAAAUAUAACUUUUCUUAAUAUAAAUUGUUAAAAUAAAUUAAAAUUUAAAAUAUGGUAUUGUUUCUCCUAUGCUGAUGUAAAUUUUCUUAAUAUAAAUUGUUAAAAUAAAUUAAUAAAAAUUUAAAGUAUGGUAUUGUUUCUCCUAUGCUGUUUCAGUGGGUACAUUUAUUUCCAUGUCUUCUGUAAAUAUAAGAAAAAUAAAUAAAAUUUAAAAGUAUAUUUGAUAACUUGCAAUAUUUGAUCCUGCAAAAGUCUUGGGAAAAUAAAAAUAAAAAGAGGAACUAUUUUCUUCAUAUUCAAUAAUGUAUUGAAAUGACUUUAACUCAGCUCACCUUUUAUCUGAUAUUGUUCCCUAAGAUUUUAACUGCUUUUAGGAGUUGAAAUGGCUCAUUCAUCCAACAAACCUUUCUUUUUCACCUACUGUAUACAAAGUCCCACAUGACCUCUCAAUAUGUUAUCAAGAUAAAGCAGACAGGGCACCCAGCCACAGAAUCUUACAAAUAUACCUUACCAAUUGCAAGUUAAAUACUACAUUGUAGGAAAGAAUUGUCUUCUGAAAUAUUAUAGGUUAGUAAUUUAUUGGCCAUCCAGAAAUGAUCAUGGUCCCUUAUUUAUCCAGAAUUUUCCUGGACCAGAUUUCUCCUCUAUAUAAUAGGAAAAGUCUAUUGGAUGCAGUUCACUAGCUGAAGUGAAUAAAGUUCAAAUAAUACAUAUUUCUUAUAUAAUAUGUUCUAAAAUCCUCAAUAACAACAUACUGAACUCUUACUAAUGCCAAAGCAAGAAUAAUAUCUAAUUCCAUUUAAAGCAUAGAAACCAGGAAAUGGAGAUCAAUAUAUUUUAAUCACUUUUUUCAUUAUGUAAUCAAAUCAAAUACUAUCAUUGCAUUAUGUAUAUGCGAAUAUAUGUUUUAACGAAUUUUGUUAAUUCAAAUUUUAAUAUAACAUUUCACCUUUUAUAAUUACUGAACAGAAUUAUUGUCAGGUUUUUGUUUGUGUUAACUUGUACAUCUUAGGAGUAUCAACCUUUUUUUUCCUUUUUUAAGUAAAAAUAAUGAAUGGCUUUACCUAUUUUGCACGCGUGGCUGUAAAAAAAGAAGUAAAGAAAAAGCAAGGAAAGAGGAAAAGUUUUAAAAAACGGGAAGGAAAAAGAGAAAAUGAACAAAUUAGUAGAACGAAGUACGGAUUUAGUGUGUAUAUGUAUGUGUAUAGAGAUGGGCUCUUCUGAGUUCUACUCUUCUGCCCAGUUGGAUCUUAAGUCUAAUCCUUAUCAUUAUCAUUAGUCCAUGCAGGGUGGGCUUUUAUGUGUUUAGUUUAUUAUUUUUACUAUUGUGAUAAGCAUCCAAGAACCCUCCACAUCCACAAAAUAGUAGGACUUUUAAAAUACAUAUAUAAAAUGAAAUAUAUAGCUACUCCCUGAAAUAUAUUCCUGCUCCUUGAUGAGUUUUUCCAAAUAUUUUUAAUUUCUUUUCCUUUUAUUAUUUUAUAGUUUGAAACUAUGAUUUUCAGUGUAUACCUUUGGAAAAUAUUCACUCUUUUUGUAUAAUUAAUACAGCAGGUGCAGCUGUUUUCUUUUUCUGUCUCCUUAAAUCUAUGGAGUGCAGCUUGGAGUGGAGGAAGAAUUUGAUAGGGCAGAGCCCUGUCUCUGCAGAUUUUUGAAGGUGCUCGUGUAUUCAGUUAGGGAAGAAACAACUUCCAGAUCUGUGCUAAUUACUCUGCUCUCUCUCUCUCUGCCCCCUGCCUGCAUCUUUCUCCACUUCUCUCUAUAUUUUUUCUUUUUCUUAUUUAUUCUUGUUAUGUAUCUUUUCUACAAGUUCUUCUCUUUCCCCAGUCAUCUUCCAACUUGUGAGUGAGAUGGGGAGGAUAAAUAUUAAGAAAGCAGAGGGUAGAAUGGUGAUUACCAGAGGCUAGGGAGUUGAGUGGAAUGGGGAGAUGGUGGUCAAAUAAUACAAAAUUUCAGUUAGACAGGAAGAAUGAAUUUUUUGUGAUGCACAACAUAGCGACUGUAGUUAAUAGUGGUGUAUUGUAUAUUUCAAAAUUGCUAAGAGAGUAAAUUUCAAAUGUUGACACCACACACACAGACACACACGCACACACACACAGAAUUCUGAUGGUGAGUAAAACCUACUUUUCAAUCCUCUUCUUCCCUUUCACAAAGUUGCAGCAAAAGGGAUGGGAUAGUGGUUACAUAAUUUACAACAUUUAUAAUUUGGCUCUAAGUCAUGAGUUAUAUUAAUACAUCUCUAAACUCUCACUUUAGAACUGAUGUUGAAUUUCUAAAUAAAAGAUAAAAUAUGACAUUUAUUUCAUGAGAGUUGAGAAUUUUGAUUUUCAUGAUUGAAAUUAUCACACCAGGAAAUUAUCACACCAAGAAGAUAUUUUUAAAAAUUCUUUCAUUGACAAAAAGAAGAGCUUCUCUUUAUGUCAGCUGGGAACAUGCUUGCAUAGUACAGGCUUCUCUUAUGAAAGAAAAUUUAUUAAAGCUCUUUCCCCUUUUAUUUUUCCCACAGAUAGCUGGCACAUGCCAUAGAAAAGAACAAGAAGUCAUUCUCAAUGUUCUGUUACUUAUUGCCCACCAUAUAAGCAGCUCCUCAAAAUUAGGGACCCUAACUAGAAUUUCAGGAAAAACCUUUAAAUAUCUUUUAUUUGAAGCAGAGGCUGUCAACUACUCUAGUAACAAGAUAAGCUCACUUAACUGGCAAAGUAUGAAGAUAAAAUUAUCCUACUAGGAUGUGCUUUAUAAAUGUCAUGAUAAAAUGCUCUUUGAUGCACUAAUUAAUUGGUACAUAAUUGGGUAGUUUUGUUCCACAGUCAAGAAUCAAUUAUAAAACGUUCCCUAUAUAUCUCCCCAUCUUUUUUUUUUUUUAAUUUGAGAUUGUCAAUAACCACGCCUCUUCUUUAACAAUUUAGGGACGGGAAGAAAUGAGGCUCUUCUGCUUCAUAAAGUUAGUACAAUGGGAGAAUAAGGGGAUCACCAUUUUGCUCUUUUCAUGAGACAGCAAAAUUUCUCUAUGGUUUGUACUUCUUCGACUGCCUUGCCAAGCAUUUUUAAAGUAGAAUCUCAUACCUUAAGACUGUUUUUUCAACACUUUAAAGACACCAUGGAGAAACUUGUAGGUAUGCCUGUAAGCUGUAUCUCUUUAAUAUUUGAACACUAAGAAUCAAAGUAUUACUACUAAGCCACUUACUGUUGUAGGGCUUUGUUUACUACUCCACAUAGGUGAAUACACAUCAAACUACAACAAUGUAUUUAAGUACUUUUCUUUUGACUAGUGCAUUCUGUUCUGGUGUUAUAAAAAUCCUGGCAGUUGUAUGUCAAUUGUCUUCUAUCUCACGUUAAAAGAUUUUAUGAGAAUCACUCAAAUUACCUUCCGUUCAUUAUCUUUACCUGUUCAAAAAUAACUUAAAUUUCAUUUGUGGUAUCUUUAAGCAAUAUGUUAUUGAUAAAGGGGUGCAUUAGAAAUGACAUCAUCUGGCAACUAGAACAAAGAGUGCUAUGUCUACACAAAGAAUACAAAUUUAUGGUUAUGUCAUGAAAUCUGGUUUUGACCAGCUGCUCUUUUUAAAUACCAAAUUUUAUAAAGAAAUAAUAAUUUUGUCUAAUAUUGUACAACAAUAGCUGGUUGUAUAUAGAAUUUACUCUCUAUGGAAGAUUUAGUAAGCACUCAUUUAGGAAGAAAACCUAUGUUUUAAAACUUGAAACAUGAUAUAAUGAAAAGAACGUGGGCACUGCAAUCACAUAGAGUUGGGUUCAAGUUCUAGAUAAGAACCUGUCUUAGCCAUCAAGGAAAUGAGAAUUUUCACUAGGCCUAUGUAAAUGUACUCAUCUUCAAUAUGGGUACUCAUCUACGCAUACAUAUGAGUCAGCUAGACUCAGCAAGGUUUGAGGAAAACCAGCCAGCAGAAUUGUUACCACAUUCAGCUACACAUGAAACACGUUUAUUUGUCUUUUUCACUAUGGCAUUGUUGCUAUUAGCCAUCAGUAAGUUAAUGAUUGUGUUAAUUGUUAUAUACCCACCUUUGGGCUGUUAAUGCAGCUAUUACAAAAAAUAUGGUAUAUUUAAAUGUACUAUCAUAAAAAUAUAAAAUAUAUUCUUAAAUGGAAAAAAGUUAAAAGCUAUAAAGUAUUAUUUGAUUUUUGUUAACAAAAGAAAAACAUGUUUAUAAUUGCAAGUAAAUCUUUAGUAAGACAUAGGAACAAUGUAUACCAAACUCUUAACAAUGGUCACCUCUGUGGAAGGGAGUGGAUGGAGAUGAGGAUGUGGUGGAGGUGGGCGUGCAUGGAGGGAAACGUCAUAUUAUGUUGUGUGCAAUUCUAUAUUGCUUGGAUUUGUUUUUAGGGUAAAAAUAUAUUCAUUUGUUGCUUCUGUAAGUAAAAUAUAAAGAAUAUAAUUGAAAAUCACUAUAGAACUUUUUUUUAAAGGAGCUAAAGUUCUUUAAAGACUGCCUAUCUGUCUACCAGAUCCACUAAAUUUUGAUUCUUUCUAGGCUCUUACUUUCUUAACCAAAGAAAAACAUGUUUUUUAGACACAGUGGGCCUGCAGUGCUCACAAUGUAAUCAAGUUAUUACACGCUAGGGAAGAAAACUCAUACCACAUGGUAUAUAUGUAAUAGAACCCCAAAGAAUGACCUAGAAAAUGAUCAUAGGAUGUCAUUAAUACCUGGGGGAUGGGACAGGGACAUUUCCUGUGAGGAGGACAAGCUUCAUUACUAGAGUGAUAAGCCAGAAUCAGACAUUUGAGGAAAGGAAAAAAACUUAUGGGAAAAAGAUAGAGAUAACAUUUAAGGUGUAUUCAGGGGACAGAGACCCGGGCAGAUGAAAUGCAAAACAAGUGAAACAUUCUGGGAAAGAUAAGGGGAGAAAAGCAAAUUGUGGAAAUUGUGAAUGGACUUGUAAACCAGACGUUAGAAUUUGAGUUGCCAGAGAAGGUGACAGGCAUUUAAAUUAGAUGCAGUACAUUGAGAUGACAGAAAAAUAUUCAGUAGUAGAAUUGGGAAUGACAACUGUGUGCAUUAAAAUUCUUAAAAAAAAAAAAAAGAAACUCACCUCGAAAACAAAACUGGAAUGUACUAAAAUGAUUAGGGUACAGCAAACCAAGAACUAAACUUUGCCCCUCUCUUGUUUCUCUGGGUGUAUCUGCAUCAUUCUUUUCUUUCUCUCUGCAGAUGAGCUUUCAUGAACUCUCAGUCCACACUGCCAUAGAUGGUCAUUCCCACAGCUCCUGCUCUGCAUGGUGUAGCCCCAUAGACAGAGAUGCAACAACUGUUCCAUGAAAAUUAUGAACACAAUCGGAAGGGUUACAUCCAAGACCUUCACAAUAGCAAAAUCCAUGCAGCCAUAACACUUCAUCCCAACAAAAGGCCUGCAUACCAAUACAGGCUGCAUAAUUACAUGCUCAGCCGCAAAAUUUCUGAACUUCGCUACCGCACCAUCCAGCUCCACAGGGAAAGUGCCCUGAUGAGCAAGCUCAGUAACACAGAAGUGAGCAAAGAGGACCAGCAGCUGGGAGUGAUACCUUCUUUCAACCACUUCCAGCCUCGGGAGAGAAAUGAAGUGAUAGAAUGGGAGUUCCUGACAGGGAAGCUUCUAUACUCAGCAGCUGAGAACCAGCCCCCUCGACAGAGCCUCAGUAGCAUUUUAAGAACAGCACUGGAUGAUACCGUCCUACAGGUGAUGGAGAUGAUCAAUGAGAAUGCCAAGAGCAGAGGACGGCUCAUUGACUUCAAGGAAAUUCAGUAUGGCUACCGCAGAGUUAACCCCAUGCACGGGGUGGAGUACAUUUUGGAUUUACUCCUUUUAUACAAAAGACACAAGGGAAGGAAACUGACUGUGCCAGUGAGACGUCAUGCCUAUCUUCAGCAGUUGUUCAGCAAGCCUUUCUUCAGAGAGACCGAAGAGCUAGAUGUCAACAGUCUUGUGGAGAGUAUUAACAGUGAAACUCAGUCAUUCUCCUUUAUAUCUAAUUCUUUAAAGAUAUUAUCUUCUUUUCAAGGUGCCAAAGAAAUGGGAGGGCACAAUGAAAAGAAAGUACACAUUCUCGUUCCUCUCAUCGGAAGGUAUGACAUUUUCUUGAGAUUCAUGGAGAACUUUGAAAACAUGUGUCUUAUCCCAAAGCAGAAUGUAAAGUUGGUCAUUAUCCUUUUCAGUAGGGAUUCUGGCCAAGACUCCAGCAAGCAUAUUGAGCUGAUAAAAGGGUACCAGAACAAGUACCCCAAAGCAGAAAUGACCCUGAUCCCAAUGAAGGGAGAGUUUUCCAGAGGUCUUGGUCUUGAAAUGGCUUCUGCCCAGUUUGACAAUGACACUUUGCUGCUAUUUUGUGAUGUUGACUUGAUCUUCAGAGAAGAUUUUCUCCAACGAUGUAGAGACAAUACAAUUCAGGGACAACAGGUGUACUAUCCCAUCAUCUUUAGCCAGUAUGACCCAAAGGUAACAAACGGGGGAAAUCCUCCCACUGAUGAUUACUUCAUAUUCUCAAAAAAGACUGGAUUUUGGAGAGACUAUGGAUAUGGCAUCACCUGUAUUUACAAAAGUGAUCUUCUAGGUGCAGGUGGAUUUGAUACCUCAAUACAAGGCUGGGGACUAGAAGAUGUAGAUCUCUACAAUAAAGUCAUUCUAUCUGGCUUAAGGCCAUUCAGAAGCCAAGAAGUAGGAGUGGUGCAUAUUUUCCAUCCAGUUCAUUGUGAUCCUAACUUGGACCCUAAGCAGUAUAAGAUGUGCUUAGGAUCCAAGGCAAGUACUUUCGCCUCAACCAUGCAACUGGCUGAACUCUGGCUUGAAAAACAUUUAGGUGUCAGGUACAAUCGAACUCUCUCCUGACAGUCCAGGCAACACAUUUUGCCUUUUUUAAGGGGAGUUUACCUCAUUGUUGGUUGUUGUUAUUUUUAUUGUAUUAUUGUUAUUUUAUUAUUAUUAUUGUUAUAAUUUUAUUUUGUUGUCCUGGUCUUAAACUACUCUUGGUUGUCUUCCUAAGGGUGUUUGUUGACCUCAAGCAAGAAGAGUCUGCAGUUCACUGAUGUUUCAGAUUUCUACUGAAGUCAAUAUGUUAUUACUUUUAUAUAACUUUAUUUGAGAUUGAGUUAAAUCAUAGCAAUCAAAUGACUUUUGAAACGCAUUCAUCACAAGAGACAGCUUAGAAGAAUGUUCUCUUGGGGCUUAAAGAUGCAAUAUCGACUUUUAUUUGGUUUCUCAAAUUCAAUGUGAUACAAAUAUUUACUGGUGAAAGGUACCACAAAAGUGCUUUAUGCUUCCUAUGGGGAAGGGACUCUGUAACAUAAACUUGAGUUUUGUAAUUUAUACAAGGACUUAAAUAUAUAAACAAUAAUUUUCUUCAUCUUUAGAAUUUUUAAAGUAAAUGAAUACCUAUGAUUGUAUGUUUAUUUUUUAAAAAAAGUUUUAAAAAUUGAGGAGUUUUGUUCCACAAGCAACCGGUACUGGCUACCCUGGUCUUAUGACAAUUAUGAGCUCCUCACAACUGUCUGCUAUAAAUGCGAAUGAACUUUAUUUUCUCAAGGAAAUAUGAUUUAAUUAAAUAUUCAUGUACAUUUUAGAAGCUUUAUGAAACAAUGUCCUUCAUUUGCUGGCAAGAAGAUAAAAUAUGACAGAACCUGUUUAUUUAAAAUAAAACACAGGUAUAGCAGUAUUCUUUUUCAAAAACACUGA